GCUGUCUGUACAUCGGCGCCCUCCGAUCUGGGGUGCGCGCCCCAGCUUGGGACACCGGGCGCUCAUUCUAGGACUUCAGGCUGGAGGCACAUUAAGGCUGCCCCCUCGCUUUGCAGACUGGCCCCAGAGAUGCUAAGUGACUUGCUAAUGGUGCCCCCGCCAGUUAACUGCUCGGACCUGCAUUUUUCAUUCGAGAAAACGGAAACCCAGAAGAUUAAGAUCUUUGAAUGCUACCUAGCAGAAGGAGAACUUCUGUUUAUAACUACAGCUUGGGAAUUCCCUGCAGGGUUUCUCCAUUCUCUGGGUAAGAAAAAUAGUCCCAAAAGCAUCCUGAGGACAGCUCAGAGAAGGUCCUAGUGAAAGAGUACCUUUCUUGCUUCUUGUAUCCCUUCAGGAAAAAGUGUUUGGAAAGUUCUGUGCCAAGAAGUUCCUCCCUAUGUCCUUGCUGUUUAGGCUUUUGAUAAUCUUUAUUGUGGAGGCCAUGCCUAAACUAAGAAAAUGCAAUACUCUCCAUGGACCUAAUGAAAUGAGAUAAUGCACAAGAGAGAGCCUCCCACAAUGCCUGGUACAUAGGGAGAGGAACAGCCUCGCCAACAUUCCCACAGGCUUGAGGAAGGUAGGAAGGAGGGGCCUCCAGCCCCCGCCCUGGUGUGGAUGUUCCCCUCCCUGCUGGGAUUACAGGUGUUGCCACCAGGCGACUGAAACAUGUCUUUUGCACUUACA